CUCCUUGCCGCCCAGCCGGUCCAGGCCUCUGGCGAACAUGGCGCUUGUCCCCUGCCAGGUGCUGCGGAUGGCAAUCCUGCUGUCUUACUGCUCUAUCCUGUGUAACUACAAGGCCAUCGAAAUGCCCUCACACCAGACCUACGGAGGGAGCUGGAAAUUCCUGACGUUCAUUGAUCUGGUUAUCCAGGCUGUCUUUUUUGGCAUCUGUGUGCUGACUGAUCUUUCCAGUCUUCUGACUCGAGGAAGUGGGAACCAGGAGCAAGAGAGGCAGCUCAAGAAGCUCAUCUCUCUCCGGGACUGGAUGUUAGCUGUGUUGGCCUUUCCUGUUGGGGUUUUUGUUGUAGCAGUGUUCUGGAUCAUUUAUGCCUAUGACAGAGAGAUGAUAUACCCGAAGCUGCUGGAUAAUUUUAUCCCAGGGUGGCUGAAUCACGGAAUGCUAUAGCAACUAGAUUCCACCACUUUGGGCUUUUACACAGAACUACAGUAUGAUCAGCUUGGUUGAAGUUUGGCACUCGACACUCUGCUCAAUUGAAGACAUAUGCACAAAAUCACUUACCACAUUUUUUAACCUGUUUUUCACACUGGGUAGGCCUGUAAUAUUUGCAUAAAAAUAUGAAAAGCAACCUUCUGCAGGGAGAGAAGGCAAUUAAAAGAUGUUGCGACCUUUCUUUCUGCAGCAUUUCAAAGCUUAAAGUUUUCUUGGCACGCUUUUCAAACGCCCAUCUGACUUUGAAGCAGGCUGCCUCUCCACAGAAAGCUUGCUCCAGCAAUGACUAAAGGAUUGACCUGGUGCCAUGCAUGCUGCUCUGCACAAGAAGGACAUUUGGAAAUGACCUUGAAGCGAAGUUUUGCCAAGUUGAUGAAAUACGGGCCUUCAAGAAGUGCCAUUUCUCAAGCGAUGUACAGAAGGGUAUCCGCAGCAUUGUCAAAAAUUACCCCUUAAUUUGGUGUUGGAUGAACAUGAAUUUUUAACCUCCAUAAGGAAUGAUACUUGCUCUUGAUUUUAUUAGUUGCAUUUUGUAACAGGUUGGAAAAAUUAGGUAAUGGAGAACUUUGGCAUACCACUUUUGUUUCUUUUAGGUGAUUUUUAAAAAACAUUUGCUGAAGGAGAGGUUGAUGCUCAAAGGGUACAGUGAUAAAUGGAGAGACGGGAGUUUAAAAUGAAGGAUAAGCCGCAAAUGAGGAUGAAGUUAAUGGAUAGAGAAAAGAUGGGAGGAAGAGGUAUCUCUCUUUACUCGUAAGCUGCCCAUCGAUAUGAUUUAGACUCUAGGAGAGGGGCGUUUCUUUCCUCAGUAGGCACACUCAUAGAGUAAACUGUUGCCGCUGUUUAAACAUGUUAAUUGAUGUUGACACCAGUUGUUGCUAUACAGUUUUCCAUUUUACUGAGCGAUGUAUUUAUGUUGCUGCAUAAUGUCGCCUGAUUGCACUUCUCAUGCUGGUGAAGUUGGCUGACAUUUCAGGCUCUGGAUAACAUGAAGCUGUGCUUUAACCUUAUUUGGAAGUCAGGGUUAGAGUGGCACUGGAAGGUCUCCUUCAGCUUCCCUUCCUGUGACCUGCCUACUAUAACCCUGGCAAGGCUGAGACAGUCCAAGUUUGGGGCAGUCAAGGUGGGACAGCAGAAGAUUUCAGGGUACAAGUCAUCUAUUCUCUUAUGCCAGCUCUCAGAUUUGUAUAUAAAAUCUGAUUCUACACUUCUUUUAACAAAUAAUAAAUAAAUAAAUAGGACCAUCCAACCCCUCUAGAGCUCUCUAAGGAGACUGUAGAAGACUUGUGGCCACUCUCAUUUUAAAGAUUCUAAUAAUCUCCACAAAGUAAUCCUGGGAAACAUACAUCUGUAAGACCAGGGAAACAUACUGGCAAUAGCAACUUCCCAGAACAUUCCUUUUUACACUGCCUGGGAUUUUUCAAUAAGAAAUUUGGCAUUUCUGUAAAUUUAAAGUGUAUUCAGUAAAAUUAAUGCGUUUUUUUCUUAAAAGCUCAAGCCUUCCAGACUCAUCAUUUUGUAGUUAAAAAAGUAAGCCAUGCAACUGAGAUAAAAGUCAAAGUUAUAGAUUAUAACUGUUUGCACAACUGUUCACAUUUUUAACUUUUUUUAUUUUUUGGAGACUUUUUAAGAGUCUCACUGUGUCAUCCAGGCUGGAAUACACAGUGGCACUAUCAUGGCUCACCACACCCUUAAACUGCAGGGCUCAAGCAAUCCUCCUGCCUCAGCCCCCCAAGUAGCUGGGACCACAGAUGUGGACCACCACCCCUGGCUACUUUUUUAAAAAUUUUUUUGUAGAGACAAUGGGCUCACUAUGUUUCCCAAGCUAGAGACAAUGGCCUCAUUAUGUUUCCCAGGCUGGUCUCGAACUCCUGGCCUCAAGCGAUCCUCCUGCCUCAGCCUUCCUGAAGUCCUAGGAUUACAUGCAUGAGCUACCACACCCAGCCCCUGCUCACAUUUUAUAUAGUAACUUAUUUUAAGAAUAGUAAAGUAUUUGCAAAAUAGUUUUUUAAUACAGUAAUUUAUUAUAUAUUGAAAUCAAGCUUGAUGAUAUUUCAUUAGGUUUUGCUGAGUGUCAUAUGCUAAGUUAUUUGCUUAUGAAUUUUUCUCCAAUUGCCUGUAUUUGGUAAGUUUGCAUGGAAAGUUCUGACAGGAAACUCAGAAAUAUUUCAUUGUUUUACCCUACUAUCUUUUUUGAUGUGUCUUAAAGUUGAUUUGCUUUAAAUUGCAGUAUCAUCCUUUUUUUCUGUACCUAAAUGUUUUUAACUGAAGAACACAAUUUCCCUCAAAACCCUCAUCCCUAAUUUAGAGCCCUCUUAUAUUAAUAUGAGUCAUUUUAAAUGUAUUUCCUGAAACACUUCUCAACUUCGUAAAUAAAAAAGAGAUAUAUCUUAGUCCAUUCAGGCUACUAUAACAAAAUAGCACAAUUGGGUGGCUUAUAAACAACAUAAAUUUAUUUAUCAUAGUUCUAGAGCCUGGGAAGUCCAAGAGCUGGGUGCCAGCAUGGUUGGGUUCUGAUGAGGAUCCUCUUCCAGAUUACAGACUUCCAGCUUCUUGCUGUGUCCUCACAUGGUGGAAGGAACAAGUAAUCUCUCUGGAGCCUCUUUUAAAAGCCCACCAAUCCCAUUCAUUGAGGAUUCCACCCCAGUGACCUAAUCACUUCCCAAAGGGCCAUCUCCUAAUGCUAUAACCUUAGAGGUUAGGGUUUCAACAUAUGAAUUUUGAGGGGACAGAAACAUUCAGCCCAUAGCAGGAUGAGAAAAAGAAAGGAAAGUACAACAAAGAACAUCAACCAUAAGGAACACCAUGACUUCUGAUAUUUAAUAUCAUGGAUCACAGAUUGUAGGAGUCGAGAAACAGAAUAAAAAGACAAGGCCCAGGCCCAGUGAGCUUUUGAUGCUUGAGGCUCCUCAUGCCCUUGCUCUCCCACUGACCUCAGUGCUCAGCACUGGCUUUCUUCUCCUGGUGAUAUUUUCCAUUUAUCUUUUGGUGUAAACAUUUUAGAGAUGAGAGAAGUAGGGAGCUUAUCAUUAUUUAGUCUGAUCAGACAAUAUCUUCACUUUUAAGUUAUGUUCAGAAUUUCAUUGUCCUGUUCUUUUUAAGAAUCAUAUGAGAUUAUUUUUGUGUAUGUGAAUAAACUAUGAAGCAUUUUCUUACAAAAAA